AGGGGAGGGCAGGCGGCGGUGGCAGCCAUGUUGUUGUGAGUCUCUGUGUCUCACCCUCGGUACUUCGGUGGUUCGGAGGAGGAGGGGGAGGAGAAGGAGGAGGUGGGGUGGGGGGGGAGGGUGGUAGGUGGAGAAAGAAGACAUUGCCGCCACCGAAGGCGGAGGAGGGGGAGGACCGCCAAGAGCGACGCCGCCGUGUGCCCAACGGUCGGUGUCCCCGGCUGAGGCAGCGCGGCCGCAGCAGCCCUGAAACAGUCAUAACCUCAAAAAUGACUUUUUAAUUCAAAUAUAAGAUUAUACUGGGUCUUGGCCAAAGAAAAGUUUCUGUCGUAUAUUUCUGUGUUGGUGCUUUCGUGCUACAGAGGCGUAGUUGAGUAGCUGCAGCAGAGAUCAUAUGGCCUGCAAAGCCUAAAAUGUUGACUCCUACACUAGGGGUAUGAUUUAUCCCAACAGUAAGAAUGGAUUCAAAGAGCUAAGAGACCUCUCAAAAUUAUCCAGAGGUUCUUUAACUUAUGUGACCUCAUCUAUUUGGACCACUGAUAAAAACCUGAAAGUAAGCAAAAAAGGUUUGAUCUGUGGAUGAAAUGAAUCAUGAUUUUCAAGCUCUUGCAUUAGAAUCUCGGGGAAUGGGAGAGCUUUUGCCUACCAAAAAGUUUUGGGAACCUGAUGAUUCAACAAAAGAUGGACAAAAAGGCAUAUUUCUUGGGGAUGAUGAAUGGAGAGAGACUGCAUGGGGAGCUUCUCACCAUUCAAUGUCCCAGCCUAUUAUGGUACAGAGAAGAUCUGGACAGGGUUUUCAUGGAAACAGUGAAGUAAAUGCAAUACUGUCUCCGCGAUCAGAAAGUGGAGGCCUUGGUGUGAGCAUGGUAGAAUAUGUAUUAAGUUCUUCUCCUGCUGAUAAAUUGGAUUCUCGAUUUAGGAAGGGAAAUUUUGGCACUAGAGAUGCUGAAACAGAUGGACCUGAGAAAGGAGAUCAAAAAGGCAAGGCUUCUCCAUUUGAGGAGGACCAAAACAGAGAUCUUAAACAAGGAGAUGAUGAUGAUUCUAAAAUAAAUGGCAGAGGUUUGCCAAAUGGAAUGGAUGCCGAUUGCAAAGAUUUUAAUCGUACUCCUGGAAGUCGUCAAGCCUCUCCAACUGAAGUAGUUGAGCGCUUGGGCCCCAAUACUAAUCCCUCAGAAGGACUGGGGCCUCUUCCUAAUCCUACAGCUAAUAAACCACUUGUUGAAGAAUUUUCAAAUCCUGAAACUCAGAAUCUGGAUGCCAUGGAACAAGUUGGUCUGGAAUCCUUACAGUUUGACUAUCCUGGUAAUCAGGUACCAAUGGACUCUUCAGGAGCUACUGUAGGCCUUUUUGACUACAAUUCCCAGCAGCAGCUCUUUCAGAGGACUAAUGCACUAACAGUUCAACAGUUAACUGCAGCUCAACAGCAGCAAUAUGCAUUAGCAGCAGCUCAGCAGCCACAUAUAGCUGGUGUAUUCUCAGCAGGCCUUGCUCCAGCUGCAUUUGUGCCAAAUCCAUACAUUAUUAGUGCUGCUCCUCCAGGGACCGAUCCGUAUACUGCAGCAGGAUUGGCUGCAGCAGCUACAUUAGCAGGUCCAGCAGUGGUUCCACCUCAGUAUUACGGCGUUCCAUGGGGGGUGUAUCCAGCCAACUUAUUUCAGCAGCAAGCUGCAGCUGCGGCAAAUAACACAGCCAGUCAGCAAGCAGCAUCACAAGCUCAGCCUGGACAGCAACAGGUUCUCCGUGCUGGAGCAGGUCAGCGUCCUCUUACUCCCAAUCAGGGUCAGCAAGGGCAGCAAGCAGAAUCACUUGCGGCAGCUGCAGCAGCAAAUCCAACAUUGGCUUUUGGUCAGGGUCUUGCUACUGGCAUGCCAGGCUAUCAAGUACUAGCUCCAACUGCCUAUUAUGAUCAGACUGGUGCCUUAGUGGUUGGCCCUGGAGCAAGGACUGGCCUUGGAGCUCCAGUUCGGUUAAUGGCUCCAACACCUGUUUUAAUUAGUUCAGCAGCAGCACAAGCUGCAGCAGCAGCAGCAGCUGGAGGAACUGCAAGUAGCCUUACAGGCAGCACAAAUGGUCUGUUUCGGCCAAUUGGCACUCAGCCACCACAGCAGCAGCAACAGCAGCCAAGCACUAAUCUGCAAUCUAAUUCAUUUUAUGGAAGCAGUUCUUUGACUAAUAGCUCCCAGAGUAGUUCUUUAUUUUCUCAUGGACCUGGUCAACCUGGAAGUACAUCUCUUGGCUUUGGAAGUGGUAACUCUUUGGGUGCUGCUAUAGGCUCAGCCCUCAGUGGAUUUGGUUCAUCAGUUGGCAGUUCUGCAAGUAGUAGUGCCACAAGGAGAGAGUCUCUAUCUACUAGCUCUGACUUGUACAAAAGAUCUAGUAGCAGCCUAGCACCCAUAGGGCAACCAUUUUACAAUAGUCUGGGAUUUUCCUCCUCUCCAAGUCCAAUAGGCAUGCCUCUGCCAAGCCAAACUCCAGGACAUUCACUUACGCCACCGCCAUCACUUUCAUCACAUGGAUCCUCAUCCAGUUUGCAUUUAGAUAUUAGUCUUUUGAAAAAGUUCUACUUUCCUGAAAAUUCAAAGUGAGGGUCUAAUGUACAAUAAGGUAAAGACCCCCCUAUUGUUUCUUAUGUUUUUUUUAUGAAAUAUAAUGGUGUGUUUUUUCUUGUCUGUGCUUUUGAUUUGUGUGUUUUAGAGCAUCUGAAAAGUCAACUAUAUAAACAUAAUAGUGAAAGAGAAAUUUCACUAUCAAAAGAUUUGCACACCAUAAGAAAAACAUUAGUUACAUAGCUACUGAACUAGGUUAGUACACUGGUUUUUGCUUUGGUCUUUCUAUGCCUGGCCAUUUUACCAGAUAAUUAUUUCAGUGAAUUUGAAUUUAGUGUAUUUGUCACUUAAGGAAGCUUAUAGGCUUGGGCCAUAUACUUCUUUUUUGGAUAUGUUAAAGAAAAAAAAUGUUUUAGGCUUGUUGUACCCCUGAAGUUGGAGCAUUGAGAACUUUGUUUAUAUUUGUAUAUUAAAAUUGUUCCCACCCCCAAAUUAUUAAAUUGGUGAUUACCUUUUUUCCCUCUCCAGGAAGUAUUUAUCCAUGUAGAUAAUACGUUUUGAAGGGCUUUGGAUAUCAGGGGCUGUGUAUGAAUCCCUAUCUUGUCAAAGAAAUUAUUUUUUUAAAACUUUAUUUUGAAUUUUUAUAAUUCUAGUUAUUCAGCUGAAACUGAGGGAUUCUAUUGCCAGCUUUUAUGUAAUUGGAAAGAUUUAAAUCAGCUUGUGUUUUAAAAAGUAAUGUUGCUACUGUAAGCAGAUGUACUGUAAGUUAGUGAUUAUGUUUGACCACCCCCUCCAAUUACAUGGGUAUAGCUAUUUAAAAGAAAAAAACAAAAACAAGCAAAAAAACUUACUAAUACAAUAAAUGUCCAUGUAACAAAGGUAUCUGUUGCAGUGUUCAUUUUGAUUUACAUUAUUGCACACACACUGGGCUAGAUUUCUUUUUUAAAGACUCUGGUCUUCCACCCCAAAUUCUGGGCCUUUGCUCAUUUGGGGUAUUGAUACUGAACAUAUACAGCCAAUUAAUGUAUUCAAAUGGAGCCCUAAGAUCCACUUUGCAGUACUAGAUGUGUAGAUUUACCUAUCUUUAGCCUAAUACCUUUCUUCAUUUAUCAUGUAUUCUUAGUCGCAGGAGCUGCUCAGCUCCUGAUUUCUGUUAUUACUGCCCAGGCAUCCUCCCUUCAUAAGACAUGCCUAUGAAAUGGACACAAAAAUUUGGAACACAACAAAUCUAAGACUUAUCAUAAUAGUUUUUUGUUUUAUUGUUAAGAUUUUGUCAUGUCCUGUCAUCUUUUCAUAGGUAAGUUUCAGAUCAGAUUCUUGUUCAGCUCUUAACUGCUGUGUUGUGCUUUAGUGCCUGUAUAAAUGGCAGUAAAUAGGUUCUACACAGCUUGCUUAGAAAUCGGAUAUAAAUGACUUUUUAGAUGUCUCUAUGAUUGAACAGCAAUCUAGAUAUGUGCUUCUCUACCUUUCUUUAGGUUGUAAAGAAAGCAGCCUAAUAGAUGCUUAGGGAAGGAAUUCUGGUCAGUUGUGGGAAAUAAUCACCACUGGGCCAGCAUUCUGCAUUAUAGACUAACAUAGCUUCAGCUUGAAAUCUGAUAUUUUAAUACACCUCUGAUUGGAAUUAGCAAUUACCUGUGUUAUUUUCUUUUUGUGACCCCCAGUUUCCCAUAGUUUUAGUGGUGGUAUGACUGGCAACAUUGUUAACAACAAAUAGACCCAUGCCAGACUGAAAAUAACUUGAAGGAUUUCAUAAAUUUUCUUUUUGCAUACUAUUCAUGGAAAUAAUCUACUCUGCACUUCCCUAUGAAUGGAUCAUGAUGCAAGGCUGUCCAAAAAAAAGAAAAAUAUUUCUUUAUGAAUCAAGUCUCAAGGCUGAUAGUAUAAAAGACUUAUGGAAAUGGAAUUUGCAUAUUUUUAAAGUAAUUUUACUGAGCUCACAUAUCAAGAAUAUGAAAUCAUGAGAUAGAGAUAAGUUCUCUCAAUUCUCAUUAGAAUUGGUUGGAAUUAAUUCCAGAUUAUUUUUCUGGGAGAUUUUAUUUUAAGAUGUGAAUGUUACAACCAUUACAGUUACCUGUAAGGCUUGAGAUCUGCAUCCCCAAAGUAUGUUCCUUUGUUAGUGUUAGUUAUUUGAGAUUCACAGAAAAUGCCCAGUAGCAACAGUCUGUGCUGUCUUUCAAAAAAAAAAAAAAAAGUUUUCAUUUUUUAAGAUAGGCUUAUAACCAACACAUGUAUUUUUAGCAGGAUGACUAGUAAUCACUUUUGGGUUGAAGUAUAAGAAUUUCAGUGCAUAGUUUUGGGGUGUUAAUUUUUUUAUAAAAAUCUAAAACACUUGUUCAAAUUUGCAGCUCUGUUGCUUAUUCUAAUAUAUUAAAGUUAGAUGCAUGAAAAAAUUUUAUUCUUCCAUUUUUUAUAGUAUAAUAUCUGAGGUUCUAUUUCAAAACAAUAACUACAGUAUAUCAUACAUUUUAAAAUAAUUUAUUAUUAACUCUAAUCUCCCUAAUUGACUUAAAUGUCUUUAACAAUUGUUCCAUUUGAAUCACAGUCAAAAUAAGGUUCAUACAUUGCAUUUGUUUGAUAUGUCUUAAUGUGUAAUUGUUUUUCCUUCAUCUUUUUUUUCCCUUUCCAUUUAUUUGAUGAAGAAACUUUAUCCUAUUUAUUUUCCCACACUCUUGACCUUGCUGAUUGCUUCCCCAUAGUAGUAUUUAAGAUGUUCCUAUGUCUCUUUCCUGUAAACUGGAAUUCGAUCUAGAGGCUUGGUCAGAUAAUUUAUGGGUUGGUUGGUUUAUUUUGACAACAUGGGGUUCUGUUAGUUUUUGUUGCACUGUAUCGGGAGACACGUGUUUGGUUGUCUCCAUUGUGAGAUGACCAGCCUGAUCCACCUAAUGGUUUUAGCAGCCUUUGAUAAUUUUUUUUCCAGAGGUUGCAAAAUGAUAAUUUGUUAAUUGUGUCAUUCUUUAUUCAUUUAUUAUCUGGAACUUUUCUAUAAAGAAGAAUAGCUAUCCCUCAUCAGUUGUAAGGUUACAACUGAUGACAGUUCAUGUAAGAGUCAGAAUAAUGCAAGAUUCUUUCCUUUACUUUCAGAAUAAUAUUGAUGCCCUAGCAACUUUUAAAGGUGACUCGUGUUUUUAUCCUCAUUGUUAUCUACAAAUGGGUAGAUUUUGGGGAUAAUUGAUAUGUUUCAGUUCAUUGCAGUGUAAGACAUCAAUUUUAUAUCUAUUUUUGGUUCUAAAAUUACACCUUCUUUGGCCCCUUGGAGCCCCUUUAUAUUGGUUCUCCUGUUGACAACAACUUGGAGAGAGAAUGAUUUUAGGAUUAAUAGUUUAUACCCUGAAAUGCAGAGAACAGUGUAAAAUUCUGGGCUUCAGGUUCAAUAUUAAAUAUUGAGUUAUUUUCUCAUGUUGUAUUAAUCUAUAGGAGGGGGGCAAUCUACCUACAGUUGUUUUAUACAUCAUUGUCUAGGAUAGAAGUAAGCAUCUUUUUUUUUUUUUUUUUGGAGAUACUUCACUUGUUGUGAAGAACAUUAAAUAUUUCUAGUAUUGCCUUAUUUUUCUACCUGGAGCUAGCUGACUAGUUCUUUCCUUGUUUUCCUUCUUCUAAUAAACUUUUUAAAUAUAGUGUUGAUAAUUUUUUUUAACUCCAGUCUUUGUGCUCAUAGUAAUUUGAUUGAUGUGGAACUUACUAGGUAUAAAGCAGUGUUCGUAUUUUUGUUAUUUAACUUAGGUUUUGACAAACUAACGGCUUCUUGCCCUGUACCUCUUCAUUUUUGAACUAGCUAUUUUUUUCUUAACAAAAAGGGUGCUAAAGUGUAAUGUGGGCUUUGAACCCAGUAAAAUUUAUUGAAAGGGGACUAUGAAGUCUGAAGAAUGUCAUGUAUUCAGCAGGUAAACAGCUGUGCUUUAGUUUGCUGUGGAUUAUAAAAUUUCCUAACCUGUCUUCCAGUUACAGAAAAUUUUAAUAAUAGGCAAGAUAUUAUAAAUUUUUAGAAUCAUUCUGUUUAAAUUGCUGGCCUUUGGCAGACUUAGUCUUGUGCUUCUCUUAUGAUAAAAUAUUCAGAGAAGUAAAAUUAGUACUGCAAAGUUGAUAGUAAGGCCACCUGCCAUUUUUCUGAGUUUCACAUACAGUCAUUAAUGAAAGCAGAAAACAAUAUGAAUUAUUCGAAGCAUUCACUGAAAAUACUGUUAUCCUUUAGCAGUUACAGUUCUCUGUAACUGAAUAGCAUUCGAUAGUUUUUUUUCUUAAAGCACCUUCAUAUUCAUAUUUCAUUUCAUCCUAAUUGUUGGCAUAGACUGUCAGAGUGGUUUGUUGAUUAAAGAUGAAGAAAUUAAAGAUCAGUUGAUUAAUAGACUUUCCCAAACCAGUGAAUAACAGAAUUAAGGCUAGCAUCCAGUUCUGACUCGUGAUACUAUUCUUCGUUUUUCCAUUAUGCUAUUCUAUAGGAACUGAACAAUUUUACAAAGUAUAUAAAUAACUUAUUCUAAUUAGCCUCUCAGAAUCUAAUGAUUACCUCAUUAUGGUAUAAGUUAUGCUUUUCUUUGGUUAAAGUAUGUAUAGGAUUACCAGCUUUUUAGGUUCCUUUCUCAGUUUAGUUAUUCUUGAGAUUUAGAUAAAAAUACUUGUCUAAGCACAUAUGUUAUAUUUGUACUUCUUAUUUGUAAUAAGAAUACUUGUUAAUCUAAGGCAGGCAAUUUAGGGACUGUGUAUAGAGCAGCACACCCGACUCUCAACAGAAUCUUACUUACAGGUUCUCAUGUUAAUAUAAAUUGAAAAACAGCUACAACCCUCUGGUAGACCUAGAAGUAAUUUAUUUGCUGAUGAGUAGGAAAUAAUGUUUUGAAGAAAUUACGUUACUAGUUGUAUGGAAGAAUUUGUGAUGUUUGGUUUUCUGUAUAAAAAUGUCUUGAUCUUGGUUGUACUUGUUUUAGAUUACUAAUUUUUUAUUUAUUAUCCUUUAAUAACAUUAUCAGUGACAUUGUGGUUCUAAUGUCUGAGAAAGUUUUCACCAGUUAAUUUACUUAGUUAAGAUAAUCACAAACUGAAGACUAGAAAAUACUUGAUCCCAUCCUGUGUUUUGGCAUCAGAAUCACUCUGGCCACUUGUUUAAAAUGCCUCGUAGUAGACUUCACAAGGAUGUGAACAGUUUGCAAAUGUGCGGCAACAGGGUUUGCUCGUUACAAUGAUUGUGGGGAUUCUAUUGGCAUUAAAUGCCUGGUAGCCAGAUGUUAUACUUUGCAUAGUCAGCACAAAAAUAGUUUCGUCCCACUGAAAUUUUCAGUAGCCUCCACAUGAAAACACUGACUUGAAAUAAUUUGUAGCUGGCAGAGAUUAUUUUAAUCUACCAAGAAUUCACCUGUAAUUUACACCAUCCCACCAUGCUUAUAAGGUACCCUAAGGAUCAAAAGGUAGCCUUUAAAAUACAGGCAGAUGUGCUUCAUGAGAGAUUUGCAGUGUUAGCCAAAUAACAUAAAAAUGAAAGUAGCAUAUAUCUCUUAGAAUGGCUUUGAAAAGUUGUUUCUUAUAUGUAGAGAAUAUUUUCACUGGAGUUGGUUUUGUUGUGAUAUAUCUAGGAAUGGAUCCAGCAGAAGAAGUGCAAGAUCUUUUACAUUAUAAACUAUAAAAUGCUGAUGGAAGUUACAGAUGACUUAAAUAAAUGGAAGGACAUACCAUAUUUUAGGUUGAAAGACUCCCUAUUAUAAAGAUACCAGCUUUCUUCUAGUUGGUCUAAAGAUUGAACGCUAUCAAUAAAAUUAGGUUUUAAAAAGAAAUUGAUAAGCUGAUGCAAAAAAUGAAAAUGGAAAAGCAGAACCAAAAGUAGUGAAGACAGUUUUGAAAAGCAAAGUUAGAAAACUUAAUACUGCUGGAUACCAGAACUUAGAAAGCUACAGUAACUAAAACUACGGUAUUGGCACAAGGAUAAAUAAAUAGAACAGCGGAACAGAGUAGUGCAUCCAGAAAUAGACCUACUCAUUUAGAUACCUAAUGACCAAGUUGCCACUCCAGUGUAUAUGAGAAAAACAGGUGUUUCAGUGACUUGGGCAGGAGUAGUUGAAUAUCCAAAUGAGGGGGAAUGAACUUUGACUUCUGUUUCACACCACACAUACACAUAUGCACACAAACACGCUUUAUUCUCAAAGAAAUUACGUGACUUAUAUUCAUGAAGUUAGUAAGAGGCAGAACCAAAAUUUUGAGCCCACGUUUAUCUGGCUUCUUCCAGAUGUUGUACUGCUUCUCAAAGGAUGCUUUUCUAUUUAUUUAUUUAUUUAUUCAUUCAUUCAUUCAUUCAUUCAUUCAUUCAUUUGACGAAGUCUUGCUCUGCCCCCCAGGCUGGAGUGCAAUGGUGCGAUUUCAGCUCACUGCAGCCUGUCUCCCAGGUUCAAGCGAUUCUCCUGCCUCAGCCUCCUGAGUAGUGGGGAUUACAGGCGCCUGCCAGCACGCCCAGCUAAUUUCUGUAUUUUUAGUAGAGACGGGUUUUCACCAUGUUGGUCAGGCUGGUCUUGAACUCCUGACCUCAGGUGAUCCACUUGCCUCGGUCUCCCAAAGUGCUGGGAUUACAGGUGUGAGCCACCAUGCCUGGUCAGGAUGCUUUUAUUUCUAAUACCUAUCCGAAUAAAUUAAAAGGACCAUGUUUCCUAUGUUUCACAUCUUUGUAAACUUUUUAUAAAAUUGUAGUAAAAUAUAAUUUAACCUAUUGUGACUUUGUGGAAAAAGUGAGUUUGAAUGUCAGUGUUAUUGGCUUUUUUGGGUUUUUCACUUGCUAACAAUUGAUCUUUAAUCCAAAUUAAAUGCUAUUUACUUUAAGGGUCUUUUAAAUAUUUCAUUACUAAUUUUAAGUUAAAACUGAUCAUGUACAGUGGCUCAUGCUUGUAAUCCCAGCAUUUUGGGAGGCUGAGGCGGGAGUAUUGCUUGAGCUCAGGAGUUCGAGACCAGCCUGGGCAAUGUGGCGAAACCCCGUCUCUAUUAAAAAUACAAAAAUUAGCCGGGUGCGGUGACAUGUGCCUGUAGUCCCAGCCACUUGAGAAGCUGAAGUGGGAGAAUCGCUUGAACCCAGGAGACGGAGGUUGCAGUAAGCCGACGUUAUGCCACUGCAUUCCAGCCUGGGCAUGACAGAUCGAGACCCUGUCUCAGAAAAACAGAAAAGAAUCUUGUUUGUAAUACUUUAAAAUACUGUAAAUAGUAUAUAAAUAGCAAGUUUUGUUUUUAUUUCUAAUUACUGAAAGUAAUUGCUAUUUUAUCUUUUCUAUAGUUUUAUUAGACUCCUUUUUAGAAUUAUGUGAUUAAAAUUGUUACUUAUUCAAUAUUGAAUAUCUGUGUUCAAUACAAUAUUGAAGCCAGCCUCUGCUUGACUAGGAGAAAAAAACAUCCUUAUUCACUGUCAUCGAGUUUGUAGCUUUGUGGUAAAUACAGAUAAAAACAGCAGUUACAAUAUAAUGAUUGUAAUGUUCUUGUCUUAUUUCACUUUAUUUCAUAAUCUUAUUCUGUAGAAACAUAGUGAUUUCAUUGGAAUUAUUUUCCUUUAUGGGUUUUUUGAACCAAAAUUAGCACACAUUGGAUUAUAAUGGAAUUGUUUCUAGGUUUAUUUUCUCCACUAGAUUAGAAACAAGAAAGCCCAGGCCUUUUUCUACAACUAAAAAUACUCAGAUUUCAUUGAAUGUUUGGGUAAUUGAAUUUGAGUGGUUUUGUUUCUUUGUUUUAUUGAUGAAUUUAUUAUUGAGUAAGGACACUUCCUUUUUAAAAAUUACUUGGUAUCCUACAUAGAUUACUAUAUUAAAGCAUUAUUUGGCUGUUCUCAA